CUUCUUUCUCGACAAGAUGGCCACACCGGCGGUACCAGUAAGUGCUCCUCCGGCCACGCCAACCCCAGUCCCGGCGGCGGCCCCAGCCUCAGUUCCAGCGCCAACGCCAGCACCGGCUGCGGCUCCGGUUCCCGCUGCGGCUCCAGCCUCAUCCUCAGACCCUGCGGCAGCAGCGGCUGCAACUGCGGCUCCUGGCCAGACCCCGGCCUCAGCGCAAGCUCCAGCGCAGACCCCAGCGCCCGCUCUGCCUGGUCCUGCUCUUCCAGGGCCCUUCCCCGGCGGCCGCGUGGUCAGGCUGCACCCAGUCAUUUUGGCCUCCAUUGUGGACAGCUACGAGAGACGCAACGAGGGUGCUGCCCGAGUUAUCGGGACCCUGUUGGGAACUGUCGACAAACACUCAGUGGAGGUCACCAAUUGCUUUUCAGUGCCGCACAAUGAGUCAGAAGAUGAAGUGGCUGUUGACAUGGAAUUUGCUAAGAAUAUGUAUGAACUGCAUAAAAAAGUUUCUCCAAAUGAGCUCAUCCUGGGCUGGUACGCUACGGGCCAUGACAUCACAGAGCACUCUGUGCUGAUCCACGAGUACUACAGCCGAGAGGCCCCCAACCCCAUCCACCUCACUGUGGACACAAGUCUCCAGAACGGCCGCAUGAGCAUCAAAGCCUACGUCAGCACUUUAAUGGGAGUCCCUGGGAGGACCAUGGGAGUGAUGUUCACGCCUCUGACAGUGAAAUACGCGUACUACGACACUGAACGCAUCGGAGUUGACCUGAUCAUGAAGACCUGCUUUAGCCCCAACAGAGUGAUUGGACUCUCAAGUGACUUGCAGCAAGUAGGAGGGGCAUCAGCUCGCAUCCAGGAUGCCCUGAGUACAGUGUUGCAAUAUGCAGAGGAUGUACUGUCUGGAAAGGUGUCAGCUGACAAUACUGUGGGCCGCUUCCUGAUGAGCCUGGUUAACCAAGUACCGAAAAUAGUUCCCGAUGACUUUGAGACCAUGCUCAACAGCAACAUCAAUGACCUUUUGAUGGUGACCUACCUGGCCAACCUCACACAGUCACAGAUUGCACUCAAUGAAAAACUUGUAAACCUGUGAAUGGACCCCAAGCAGUACACUUGCUGGUCUAGGUAUUAACCCCAGGACUCAGAAGUGAAGGAGAAAUGGGUUUUUUGUGGUCUUGAGUCACACUGAGAUAGUCAGUUGUGUGUGACUCUAAUAAACGGAGCCUACCUUUUGUAAAUUAAUUUCAUCUUAUGUGAGUUUAUUGCCGGGUGGAAGGGAGGAAAAUGUUUUAGAUCACACAGAAACUAGGAAGUGAAUAUUGUAGGUAGAGAAGUUGGUUAUGUGUUUGGCAUGUUACUGUUUUACCAAACUGUUCUUUUGGUUUUCAAUAUGGAAAGGUGUCCAUUGGCAAAACAACCUUUUCUUGAGGAUUCAUGUGAUUUCUACAGGAAAUGAAAAUAAGAAUCCAUGGAGAAAAAAUAGCUAAGAAAAUUGGAUGCUUAAUCUGAACUAAAAGAGUAGAGUGUGUAGUCACUAUCUUAAAAUACAUUAAUAGUAAGAUGGAGCUCUUUGCCACUUUGGUUCGGGGAGGCAGAAUUAAGAUCUGUGGGUUAAAGAUUAAAGAGGUUUCCCCAAAACUUCAGAAAAUUCUUAGGUGCUAUCUGUAACUCGAGGAUAGAGCCUUGAGUUAUACUGAGGUCUGCCAGUGGCUCAAUUUAAGCAAAGACUAGAUGGCAUUUCCCAGAGGCCUUGUAGGCUAGAGUACUUGCCUGUGUAACUUCAGACAUCCAUUUCCUCUGGUAUCCUGGAGUUCCGCCUCGCCACUGUGUGUCUUAGAAAUAAGUCAUUAUUCAAGAACUCAGGAAAUUAUACGUUGGAGUGAAAAGGUGAGUGAAGGCAAUGGGGAAUCAAAAAGGCCUGGAUCCUAGUUCUGAGGUAUGUGUAGCCUUAGGAAAGAUAAAUUAUAAGAGUCAUAAGAUAUGGAUCAUAAACAUACAUAGUCCAUUAGGGUAUUAUGAGGAUUCCAUGAAUUAAUAAAUGUCAGGUUAAUCAACACUUGUGGAGAAUAUCACCUGGUAUGUAGUAAGCACAGAUAAGUGGUAGAUACUAUGAUGCCUAAAGGUGAAUAGUUUGAAAGUAAUAAGCAACAUGAACCCCAGCCUGGAACUCAGUUCUGAGAUAUGUACCUCAGGAAAUAUAAGUUAUGGGAGUCAUAAAGUGUGGAUAGUAAUGAUAGAUAAUUUCUUACAGGUAGGGAAAUGUAAACAGAUCUUAUCGGCAAAAUGAUAAUGACAGGCCAAAUUGUUAAAGGUAGGUUAAAAGUAGACAGCAUGGUGGGAAGGUUAAUCAGAGUCAAAAUGUUUCAGUGUUCUUACAUUUUUGGGAGUAGCCAGUUAAUAUCAACUUAGUCUUUUUAAGUAUGCAUGAUAAAAUUCCGAGGUUAAUUGCUAGAAGUAUAUAUAAUCUCUCAAUGAAUAGUGAUGAGAGAUGGUGGGAUAAUAGGGAAGAAACAAAAUUUUAAAUUUGAGAAAUAAGCAUAGAAAAGGUGGAUAAAACAAAAGAUGGCAAAACAAGUCCAAAUAGAUCAGUAAUUACAAUAAAUGUAUAAGUAUUAAACUAGCCCAAGGAAAAAUUGAAUAUUAAAACAAACCCCAAUCAUAUGCUGUUUACAGGAGACACAUCUAAAACAAGGACAUAAAGUUGUCCUGCAGCUGUGAGUAACAAUAUAGGUGAAUGUUAAUAAUAAUGUUGAAUGAAAAAAGCUGGUGUCAGAAGACAUGUACAUUAUGAUACUCCAGAAGUUCAAAAACAAGUGAAACUUGUUUAGACAUGCGGUUGGCUGUCUGUAUAUGUGGGUUCCACAUCUAUGGACUCAACCAACUACAGGUUGAAAAUAUUGAGGGGGAAAAUUGUGUCUGGACUAAACCUGUACAGACAUUUUUCCUUGUCAUUUUUCCCUAAACAAUACAAAGUAUUAGAUGGUGUUUAUACUGUAUUCGGUAUUAUAAGUAAUCUAGAGAUGACUUAAAAGUAUAUGAGAAGGUAUGCACAGGUUAUAUCCAAAUACUUCAUAUUAGGGACUUGAGCAUCAGAGGAUUUUUAUAUCCAAGGAAGGUUCUGGAACCAAUCCUCCACGGAUACUAAACGGUGACUGUGUGUGUAUAUAUAUAUGUAUAGUCUGUUCUCAUUAUCUAUAGUAGUUAUGUUUUAUAAAGUCACCAUGAACACUGAAUUAGAGAGUACUGAACCAUUAUUCCCAAGGGAAAUACAGGGUUGGGUUCCUAUGAACCUCUGGGCACAGUUUCAUCAACCCAUCAGUACAUAAACUUGUUACAUGUGUUUCUGUUUGAAGACACCUUAGUAUAUAUGGUUGACCCAUUAACACUGAACUUAGCCCACGACACUUAUUCCUGAAUGAAGCUUACCUCAGUUUCUCCAGGCGGCACAUCACAGUCUUCUUGCACUUAGGAACACUUGGCACUGUGCGUGGGGGUCACUUUAAGCAGCAAAAUCCACAAAAAUGCAAAAGACAUGGCACUAAAUAGACUGAAAAGGAUACUUGUUUAUAAGAACUGAAACAAGAAGGCCUUGUUCCACCUCAGCUGGGAACAUGGAGAGCAGGCAAUUCAAAUUUUUUCACAUGCUGCAUGUCCGCAAAUGGCUGCAAAAGCCCAGCAAGUACUGAUACUGGAGUUAGAAAUAAAUUUUAGCAAGAGGUAAAUUCACACAUACGGAGUCUGCAAAAAAUGAGAAUUGACUAUUAUGUGUGUGUAUAUUAUAUAUAUGAUAAAAAACAAAAGAAUGAUAAAAAUUCCCAAUAAUGUUUACUUUGGUGGUGAGAAGAGGAUGGCAAGUAAAAUAAGUCUGUAUUGUUAUCAGCAAUUAUCUAGUUUGAGGUUGGACAGUGGUUUCAUCAUAGGUAUUGAUUAUAUUAUAAAUAGCCCAACCUGAACUCAUGACCAUAGUGUGGUGUUAUUACUUAGCGUUAUUCUAGACUUAUUAGCCAUUGUAUUUAAACAAGAGGAAAUAGAGACAUUGAAGAUAAAGUGGAGCCAGGCACAGUGGCUCAUGCCUGUAAUCCCAGCACUUUGGCAGGCUGAGAUGGGUUAAUCAAGACCAGAAGUUCAAGACCAGCGUGGCCAACAUGGCAAAACCCCGUCUCUACUAAAAAAAAACAAAAAAUACAAAAAUUAGCCAGGCGUGGUGGCACGCACCUGUAGUCCCAGCUACUUGGGAAGCUGAGGCAGGAGAAUCUCGAACCCAGGAGGUAGGGGUUGCAGUGAGCUGAGAUCGCACCACUGCACCCCAGCCUGGGUGACAGCAAGAUCCUUUCUCAAGAAAAAAAGUGAAAAGGAGGAGGGUUUUUAAAAAAUUAGUACUACCCAGUUGAUACGGUGGAAGAAAACUUGAAAAUGCUAAUGAGAAACAUGAGAUGUAAUCACUUGAAGGCAUAUCAUGUUCUUGAAUAAGAAGACUCAACAUUAUUUUAACAGGUGUUAAUUUUCCCUGUUAAACUACAUAUUUGUCAUAAUUACAAUAAAAUACAAAGAGCUAUUUUGGAACUGGGCAAGCUGUUUCUAAAUGUAUAUGGAAAAAUAAAAAUGUCUCCAAAAAAUCCCUGCAGAGGGAAACUAGCCCUUCCAGAUAUAAAAUAUAUUAUAGAACUGUGUAAUUAAAGCAAUAUGGUACUGGUCCAUAAAAGAACAUAAAACCAAAUAGUUCAGUAGACUCAAAAUGCAAGCGUUGGUGAGGGUAUGGAGAAAAGGGAACCCUUUUACACUUGGUGUGAAUGUAAAUUAGUACAGACAUUGUGGAAAACAGUUUGUAGAGCUUCCUCAAUAAAAACACAUAUGAUCCAGCAAUCCCACUACUGGGUAUAUAUCCAAAGGAAAUGAAAUCAGUAUGUUGAAGAGAUACUUCCACGUUCACUGAAGCAUUGUUCACAAUCGCCAAGACAUCAACCUAAGUGUCCAUCAACAGAAGAUAGAUAGGGCUGAGCGCGGUGGCCCACGCCUGUAAUCCCAGCACUUUGGGAGGCCAAGGCAGGUGGAUCAUUUGAGGUCAGAAGUUCUUGACCAGCCUGGCCAACAUGAUGAAACCCCGUCUCUACAAAAGAUACAAAAAUUAGCCAGGCAUCUUGGAGGGCGCCUGUAAUCCCACCUACUCGGGCUGAAGUGAGAAUGGCUUGAACCCAGGAAGUGGAGAUUUCAGUGAGCUGAGAUUCCGCCACUGCAGUCCAGCCUGAGCGACAAGAGUGAGAAGAGUGAGACUUCAUCUCAAAAAAAAAAAAGGUACAUCUACACAAUGGAAUAUUAUUAACCUUAAAAGAAGGAAAUAACUGAUUUACAACAACAUGGAUGGACCUGGAGGACACUAUGCUAGUGAAAUAAGCCAUGAUCUCACUUGGAUAUGGAAUCACAAAAUUGAACUCACAAGCAGAGUGUAGAAAGGUGGUUUCAUGGACUGGAGGGAGGGGAUAAAUGGGGAGAUGUUGGUCAAGGGUACAAAGUUUCAGUUAAACAGGAGUAGUACGUUCCGGAGACCUGUUGUGCAGCAGGGUGACUAGUUAAUGUAUACUUGAAAAUUGCUAGGAGUAGAUCUCACCAGGAGAAAUGAAUAUGUGAGGUGAUGGAUGUAACUAGCUUGAUUGUGGUAAUCAAUUUCGCAAUGUGUACAUAUAUCAAAACAUCACAUUGUACAAAAUACAUACAGUUUUUGUCAAUUUAAAGAUAUCAGAAUUCUAGAAUAUGAUAAAGUUGUGUUUUCAAGCAAGUAAAGAUAGAUUACUUAAGAGCGAAUGAGUGGUAAUUUGGAAACAAUGUUGGAUUCCUACUUCGUUACCUGCACCAAAAUAAGUUGCUCAUGGAAUAAAAACUUGUCUGAAAAAAAAACCAUAAAUAUGAGGGAAAAAACACAGCAAUGUGUUUUUAAUGAUUUAUGAGUGAGGAAGAACUUUCUAAGAACUGAGAAUCCAGGAGUUAUUUUAAAAGACUGACAAAUUUAGCAACAUUUUUAAAAUCUGAGUGUCAAAUUACACACAUACACAAAUAGUCAAUACAAAUAUAAAACUGGGAAAAUAUUUGCAGUUCAUAUCAAAAAAAGGGCUAAUAUUCUUGUCCCAGAAUUCCUACAGUUUUUUAAGGCCAGUAAUUUGAUACAUUAGUGUGUAAAGGAUAUGACCAGACAGCUCACACACAGACACACAAAUGUGAAAAGAUGCUUGAUCUCACUGAUAAAGCAUAAAUUAAAACGAUGUCAUUUUUAAAAAUCAGAUUCGCAAAUUUUAAAAGUUGCUAACACUGGAAUGGCCAGAGUAAGAGGAAACGUGACACAGGCACAGAUUGCUGGUAGACAUAUAAGUUGGUACAGCCCUCUCUAUGUAAUUUUGUGUUUGUCAAAAUUACAAAUAUGCAUGCCCUUAACCCAGGAAUUCCACUCCUCAUUAUAUAUCCUACAAAUAAACUGGUCUCGUUAUGACACAAUGUAAUGAAUACAUAGAUAAGUACUGAAAUACUUGGUUAUCAUAGCGUAAAGAUGGUAAUCAACCCAAAUGACUAUUACCAGAAUAGAAAUUAAACAAAGUAUGAUAUAUCCAUAAAACACAAUACUAUGCAGCUGUUAAGCAGAAUGAGACAGUCCUCUAUAUAUCAAUAUGGAUAAAGAGUAAGUGAAAAAAGCCAGGAGAGAAUGUUGUCUAUAAUAUGCUGUUGUUGUGUACGGGAAAAUAAAUAAUAUAAAUACCUAGAAUAUUUGUGAAGGUACAGCCAAGAAACUACUAUCACUGAUUGUCUUAAGGUACUAGAUGGGGCACAGGACAGGACGAAAGAUUUACUUCUUAUUGUUUCUUCUGUAUAACUUUUGAAUUUUAUGCUGUUAAUGUAAUUUUUCAAAAAAAUAUAUAAAAAUAUAAAAACAUGAAAAA